ACUCCCGGAAGCAGAUUGCGCCAGGGAAAGGCCUUAUCGCUGUGUGUGUGUUUCAGUCUACGUGGAUUAAACAUUACUUCGCUCCGUCUGCCUGGAUUAAACGUGCACUUUGCAGUCCUCACUUCUCCGUACCAGUGAUCUGGGGAUCGCUACGGACCUUAAAAUACCCAUAGCCCCUUCGCCCCUGCAACAGGCACUUCUCCCCACGUCGUGUUCCUGCUUAAAACUCUCAUUGACCCCUGCUUCGGCCCCGGGCGAAGUCAAGUCCUCCCUCGCGAGGUGGAUUCCCACCAGUCGAGACCCCCGAGCUUCGCCCUUGUCGACGCCUGGAGGGGAGCGCCCGCUGCCCAGCUCCUGAAGGAGCCGCUUCUUCUCCCAGGUUUGAUGUGUGAAUAAUUACAUUGACUGAGAAAGAAACCCAGAAGAGGAAGAAGAGGAAGGAAAAGGAGUCAGUGAUGGCUACUCAGGGGCAUUUGACAUUCAAGGAUGUAGCCAUAGAAUUCUCUCAGGAGGAGUGGAAAUGCCUGGAGCCUGUGCAGAAAGCUUUGUACAAGGAUGUGAUGUUGGAGAACUAUAGGAACCUGGUCUUCCUAGGUAUCUCUCCUAAAUGUGUGAUCAAGGAAUUACCACCAACAGAGAACAGUAAUACAGGAGAAAGGUUCCAAACAGUGGCACUGGAAAGACAUCAAAGCUAUGAUAUUGAAAAUUUAUACUUCAGGGAAAUACAGAAACAUCUACAUGACCUUGAAUUUCAAUGGAAAGAUGGUGAAACAAAUGAUAAAGAAGUGCCAGUGCCCCAUGAAAACAAUCUUACUGGUAAAAGAGAUCAACAUAGUCAAGGGGAUGUAGAAAACAAUCAUAUUGAAAACCAGCUUACAUCAAACUUUGAGUCACGUCUGGCUGAACUGCAGAAAGUUCAAACUGAAGGGAGACUUUAUGAAUGUAAUGAAACGGAGAAGACAGGUAAUAAUGGUUGUUUAGUUUCUCCACACAUUAGGGAAAAAACGUAUGUAUGUAAUGAAUGUGGCAAAGCCUUUAAAGCGUCUUCCAGCCUUAUUAAUCAUCAGAGGAUACAUACUACAGAGAAACCUUACAAAUGCAAUGAGUGUGGCAAAGCCUUUCAUCGGGCCUCACUACUAACUGUACACAAGGUAGUCCAUACAAGAGGGAAAUCAUAUCAAUGUGAUGUAUGUGGCAAGAUCUUCAGAAAAAAUUCAUAUUUUGUAAGACACCAAAGGAGUCACACUGGACAGAAACCCUACAUAUGUAAUGAAUGUGGCAAGUCCUUUAGUAAAAGUUCCCACCUUGCAGUUCAUCAGAGAAUUCAUACCGGUGAAAAACCUUACAAAUGUAAUCUGUGUGGGAAAUCCUUUAGUCAGCGUGUCCAUCUUAGACUUCAUCAGACAGUUCAUACUGGAGAGAGACCCUUCAAAUGUAAUGAGUGUGGCAAAACCUUUAAACGGAGCUCAAACCUCACUGUACAUCAGGUAAUCCAUGCAGGAAAGAAACCAUAUAAAUGUGAUGUAUGUGGCAAGGCAUUCAGACAUAGAUCAAAUCUUGUAUGUCACCGGAGAAUCCACAGUGGAGAGAAACAAUACAAAUGCAAUGAAUGUGGCAAGGUCUUCAGUAAACGUUCAAGUCUUGCAGUGCAUCGACGAAUUCACACUGUAGAGAAACCUUGCAAAUGCAAUGAAUGUGGCAAGGUCUUCAGUAAACGUUCAAGUCUUGCAGUGCAUCAGAGAAUUCAUACUGGACAGAAAACUUACAAAUGCAAUAAAUGUGGCAAGGUGUACAGUAAGCAUUCACAUCUUGCAGUGCAUUGGAGAAUUCAUACCGGCGAGAAAGCUUAUAAAUGCAAUGAAUGUGGCAAAGUUUUCAGCAUACAUUCACGACUUGCAGCUCAUCAGAGAAUUCAUACUGGAGAGAAACCUUACAAAUGCAAUGAAUGUGGCAAGGUCUUCAGUCAACAUUCACGUCUUGCAGUGCAUCGGAGAAUUCAUACUGGAGAGAAACCUUACAAAUGCAAAGAAUGUGGCAAGGUCUUCAGUGACCGUUCAGCUUUUGCAAGGCAUCGGAGAAUUCAUACUGGAGAGAAGCCUUACAAAUGCAAAGAAUGUGGCAAGGUCUUCAGUCAAUGUUCACGUCUUACAGUGCAUCGGAGAAUUCAUAGUGGAGAGAAACCUUACAAAUGCAAUGAAUGCGGCAAGGUCUACAGUCAGUAUUCACAUCUUGUAGGGCAUCGAAGAGUUCAUACUGGAGAGAAACCAUACAAAUGUCAUGAAUGUGGCAAAGCCUUUAAUCAGGGCUCCACACUCAAUAGACAUCAGAGAAUUCAUACCGGAGAGAAACCUUACAAAUGCAAUCAGUGUGGGAAUUCCUUUAGUCAGCGUGUCCAUCUUAGACUUCAUCAGACUGUUCAUACUGGAGACAGACCUUACAAAUGUAAUGAGUGUGGCAAAACCUUUAAACGGAGCUCAAACCUCACUGCACAUCAGAUAAUUCAUGCAGGAAAGAAACCAUAUAAAUGUGAUGAAUGUGGCAAGGUAUUCAGGCAUAGUUCACAUCUUGUAAGUCACCAGAGAAUCCACACUGGAGAGAAAAGAUACAAAUGUAUUGAAUGUGGCAAAGCCUUUGGGCGGUUGUUUUCCCUCAGCAAACACCAAAGAAUUCAUUCUGGCAAAAAACCUUAUAAAUGUAAUGAGUGUGGGAAAUCUUUUAUUUGUCGCUCAGGCCUCACUAAACAUCGAAUAAGACAUACUGGAGAGAGCCUUACAACUAAACUCAAUGUGACAAGGCCUUAGACGUUGUCCUAGUUUCUGGAAUCACCGAAUAAUUCCUACUUACUGAUAUACCUUGUAUAUUUACCCCUUCUCUUGAAAUCCCUGUGGAAUUGUAAUCUCCAGUAUUGGAGGUGGGGCCCAUUGGGAGGUGAUUGAAUCAUGGAAGUGGAUUUCUCAAACUGAGAAAGAUGUAGCGUCAUCCCCUUGGUGCUGUCCUGGCAAUAGUGACUUCUCUUGAGGUCUGGCUGUUUAGAAGUGCAUAGCACUUCCCUGUCGCUUGCCCUCAUUCUCACCAUGUGAAAUACCGACACCCGCUUUGCCUUCCACCAUGAUUUUAACCUUCCUGAGGCUUCCCUAGAGGGUGAUCAGAUGCCAGCACCAUGUUUUCAUUUAAGCCUUCAGAAAUAUGAGCCAAUUAAACUCUUUUCUUUAUACAUUAGCCAGCCUCAGGUUUUUUUUUGUAGCAAUGCAGUUAUGACCUAAUACAUUUACACAUGCAGUAAAUAUACCUAAGUUUUAAGCUAGUAUUCACUACUCACUAGGUGUAAGAAUUUGUAUAUAUAUUCCAGGAUGUAUACAUCCUGGAGAAAAAUCACAGAAGUGUAAUACGUGUGGCAAGAAUUCUACUCAAAAGCCAGAACUUGUAAAUCUAGGUAAUUAAAAGGGCAUAGAUGUAUGAAAUGAAAUGAGGGUGGCAAAACCUUUACUAGAGUUCAAUCACUACUUGUCAUAAGAGAGUUUAUACUGAAAGGAAAUCAUAUAAAUGUAUGUGUCAGAGGCUUUCCCCAGGCAUUGGAACUCACUAGGCAUCAGAAUAUACAUCUUUGAGAGGAACCACAGAAAUGUAAUGUGCAUGCUAAGGUUUUUACCCGAACAUCAAAAUGGAAAGAGUAUUCAUACUAGAGACAACCUUCCAAAUAAAUGGUUUUAAAAAAUGAAAUGUUCAAAGACCUGGAAUCAACCCAAAUGCUUAUCAGUGAUAGACUGAAUAAAGAAAAUGUGGUACAUAUACACCAUGGGAUACUAUGCAGCCAUAGAAAGGAAUGAGAUCAUGUCCAUUGCAGCGAUGUGGAUGGAGCUGGAAGCCAUUAUCCUCAGGAAACUAACACAGGAACAGAAAAUCAAACAGCACAUGUUCUCACUUAAAAGUGGAAGCUGAACAAUGAGAACACAUAUACCCAGGGAGGGGAGCAACACACACUGGGGCCUGCUGAUGGGGGUGGGAAGGGCAGGGAAGUGGAGCAUCAGGACAAAUAGCUAAUGCAUUUUUGCCUUAAUACCAGGUGAUGGGUUGGUAGAUGCAGCAAACCACCAUGGCACACAUUUUCCUAUGUAACAAAUUUGCAAAUUGUGCACAUGUACCCAGAACUUAAAGUGAGACAAAACCAAUGUCCACGCCUUUGCAGUUUGAUUGAACGUAUAAAGGAGAAAAAUCCUGUAAGUAUGCUGAACAUGAAAGGACCUGGAAGCAGUAGUGUGUCUUCAGCCUUUACCAAAUUAUCCCUACUUGAGAGAAAACUUGGAAAUGUAAUCAAUGUGGCACAAAUUUCAACCAGUUUUUUAAACAGACUACACAUCUUUGAAAUCAUACUAGGGAUAACCAAAUCUGCUUCUCCAAGAUUGGCCUGGAAUAUUAUUACAGAAUAACUACCAGACAACAUUUGUUAAAACUCAGGACAGUAUGUAUUUUAAAGGAGCAAGUGCAUGUGUGAAAAUGGCUCAUUCAGUUUAUAAAAUAUUACAUUAAA